UUUUCAAAGUCUACUUUUAAAACAGUAAAGUUAACUUUUCUCUCUAGUAUUUGUUUUGUAGAAUCUAUUAUACUUUGUAAUGUAAUCCACAGAAACUUGGAGGUGACUUUAGUAAAAUUUACUAGUUUUGAAUGAUACCCAUGCUGAGGUGCUCAGAGGUGAAAUGUACUAACAUAUAUCGAUGGAUGGAUAUAUGGAUGCAUAUGUGAUUAAAGCAAAUAUAGGGAAAAUUAACUGUAGAAUCUAGGUAGUGGGUAUAUGGUUGUUCACUGUACAACUGUUUAAACUUUUCUACGUUUGAAAAAUUUCAUAACACGUUGGAAAAGUGACUUGUUUUGCUCAAGCAGGGGUACAUUCAAUCUUCAAUUCUUGAAAGACAUAAAUCUAUCUUUCCUUCUGUUUGGAAAGCUCUUUAGAGAGUCAGAAUAAUCCCCACAGUACAGUCUAAACCAGCACACAAGGGUUUUUUGGUAGAAAAUAAUUUUAUUAACAUAACCAGGCAAUUUACCAAAUACAACGUAGAUAGCUCAAAACAUGGAGUUACUGCGCUGAAAAUGUGACCCUGUUUACACAGAUUUCGGGACGAAGAGUAUAAAACAGGAGAGAAAAGGAGUAAGAUUGUGGUUGUAGCGUCAUCGCAGAGGUGAAGUGUUCCAUUGAUUGCCACUGUGGUAGUCUAUAUCAGUUUCCCACAUUAAGGUGGGAGGAAUCUACUAAGCAAAUGUACGCCCUCCCCAUUCGUUCGAAACACAUUGCAGUAAAAUUGCAAAAGUGGCCGGGCGUGGUAGCUCAUGCCUGUAAUCCCAGCACUUGGGGAAGCUGAGACGGGAAGAUCGCCUGAGGCCAGGAGUUUGAAGCCAGCUUGGGUAACAUAGUGAGACACCCCUACCUUCUCUAUUAAAAUGAGAUUUUAAUUUUUUUUCUCUUCAGUUCAUCGGUUAACAAGAUAAAAAAAUUAAUAAAAAAUUAACUUUUUAAAACAUUUAAAGUAAAGUAGGAGUGGAAGCAGUAUGUGGACUCAUGGGGCUUGGGUCUGAAUCCUACCUAGAUCGGCACUGCGAAAUGGGGAUAAUGAUCUCCUAGAGCUGCUGAAAUAGGAAAAUGGAAGAACAGCAGCUGAUGUAUUAAUAUUAUCAUUAUUACUACUACCCAUUACCUGACAAGUGAUAAUUGUGACAUGAAAGAGGCUGGACCGGUUGUUACAACAAUUUUUUCCGUCUAGAAUUCGGCGGUAAGGUCUGAGACAACACCUCAGCUUAGAUCAGUGCCUUCUCUGAACAGCGUUCACUAAGCAGCCCCCAACCCCAAAACCCCCAAGUCCCCGGGCGCCGAGGACGCUGCGAGUCCUGCGCAUGCGCAAGGUUGCCCACUCGCUCACCGCCUCCUUGGCGAAUGGCCUGUUCCAUUCUCGAGGGAUGCCGGCGGGAGGUGAGGCGGGAGACUUGGAAGCCUGGGCCCGGAAGUGAGAUAGCAGACCCCACGUUAGCUGAAAUGGGAAAAAACUUGAAGGAGGCAGUGAAGAUGCUGGAGGACAGUCAGAGAAGAACAGAAGAGGAAAAUGGAAAGAAGCUCAUAUCCGGAGAUAUUCCAGGCCCACUCCAGGGCAGUGGGCAAGAUAUGGUGAGCAUCCUCCAGUUAGUUCAGAAUCUCAUGCAUGGAGAUGAAGAUGAGGAGCCCCAGAGCCCCAGAAUCCAAAAUAUUGGAGAACAAGGUCAUAUGGCUUUGUUGGGACAUAGUCUGGGAGCUUAUAUUUCAACUCUGGACAAAGAGAAGCUGAGAAAACUUACAACUAGGAUACUUUCAGAUACCACCUUAUGGCUAUGCAGAAUUUUCAGAUAUGAAAAUGGGUGUGCUUAUUUCCACGAAGAGGAAAGAGAAGGACUUGCAAAGAUAUGUAGGCUUGCCAUUCAUUCUCGAUAUGAAGACUUCGUAGUGGAUGGCUUCAAUGUGUUAUAUAACAAGAAGCCUGUCAUAUAUCUUAGUGCUGCUGCUAGACCUGGCCUGGGCCAAUACCUUUGUAAUCAGCUCGGCUUGCCCUUCCCCUGCUUGUGCCGUGUACCCUGUAACACUGUGUUUGGAUCCCAGCAUCAGAUGGAUGUUGCCUUCCUGGAGAAACUGAUUAAAGAUGAUAUAGAGCGAGGAAGACUGCCCCUGUUGCUUGUCGCAAAUGCAGGAACGGCAGCAGUAGGACACACAGACAAGAUUGGGAGAUUGAAAGAACUCUGUGAGCAGUAUGGCAUAUGGCUUCAUGUGGAGGGUGUGAAUCUGGCAACAUUGGCUCUGGGUUAUGUCUCCUCAUCAGUGCUGGCUGCAGCCAAAUGUGAUAGCAUGACGAUGACUCCUGGCCCGUGGCUGGGUUUGCCAGCUGUUCCUGCGGUGACACUGUAUAAACACGAUGACCCUGCCUUGACUUUAGUUGCUGGUCUUACAUCAAAUAAGCCCACAGACAAACUCCGUGCCCUGCCUCUGUGGUUAUCUUUACAAUACUUGGGACUUGAUGGGUUUGUGGAGAGGAUCAAGCAUGCCUGUCAACUGAGUCAACGGUUGCAGGAAAGUUUGAAGAAAGUGAAUUACAUCAAAAUCUUGGUGGAAGAUGAGCUCAGCUCCCCAGUGGUGGUGUUCAGAUUUUUCCAGGAAUUACCAGGCUCAGAUCCGGUGUUUAAAGCCGUCCCAGUGCCCAACAUGACACCUUCAGGAGUCGGCCGGGAGAGGCACUCGUGUGACGCGCUGAAUCGCUGGCUGGGAGAACAGCUGAAGCAGCUGGUGCCUGCAAGCGGCCUCACAGUCAUGGAUCUGGAAGCUGAGGGCACGUGUUUGCGGUUCAGCCCUUUGAUGACCGCAGCAGGAGCACCGACCAAUCAGAACAGACACGGUGACCAAACAGGCACAGCCACACCAGUGGAUACCAGCGGAAUGUCCACGCUGCCUCUGCGAAGGGACAGUCCCAUGAGCCAAGCCCUAGACCAGCUGUUCUGGGAGCACUGCAUCAUUGCACUGAAUUCUCACAACCGCCCCAUAAUGCUGGGACCAUCCCCAUUUUCUUGCCCAACAGCCUUCGUCUCAUAGACACUAGGCGGCUCUCCCAGGGUCACACGGUCCAGUCAAUAACGGGCAGAACUCGCACUCCGAUCUGUCUGGCUCCAAAGCUGCUAAAAAUUUUCUACUUGGCCUCACUGGCUUGACAAAGAUAAAAAAGAAGGCAAGUCCUUCUUUCCAAGAGAUGCUGAGGUCCCUCGGUGACACUAGGUCAUGAUUUUAUCAUGUUCAGAGGGCAAUGAAAGGGACAGAAAACAAGCGAUGUGUGAUCUCCUGUCAUGUCAAGAGACGCUGUUUUCAAAGAAACGUACGUUUCGCAGAAUCAAUACGCUGUGGGGCCUCAGAAAGCAGAGGCAGACACACGGCCCCAACCCGUGCACGUGGGAGCCCUGUUACAAGAGACGGCAGAAAUUAAACUGAAUCACCUGGAGCAAGUACAUUGUAAAUGUUCAAUAUUAAUGACCCACCUCGGCCCCAAAGAAGAGAGCGUUGGGCUUUGUCCAGCUGUGUGCUCUGUUGUUAAAAGACCACCUUGUGGCCAGGCACGGUGGCUCACACCUGUAAUCCCAGCGCUUUGGGAGGCCAAAGCAGGUGGAUCACCUGCGGUCAGGAGUUCGAGACCAGCCUGGUCAACAUAGUGAAACCCCGUCGCUACUAAAAAUACAAAAAUUUGCUGGAUGUGGUGGCUGGCGCCUGUAAUCCUAGCUACUCGGGAGGUUGAGGCAGGAGAAUCGCUUGAACCUGGGAGGCGGAGGUUGCAGUGAGCCAAGAUCACGCCAUUGCACUCCAGCCUGGGCGACAAGACUGAAACUCCGUCUCAAAAACAAACAAACAAACAAACAACAACAGAAAACAAUUUGUGCCUUAAUGGGCAUUCCUUUCCCUUCUUGCUAAGGGAUGAGAUGAUGGCAGAACUUGUGGCCACUGUCCUGGAGGUUGACAAGCUUUUUCUGUAAAGUGCUAGAUAAUAAAUAUUUUGUGGGCCACACGAUCUCUGGUGCAACUACUCAACACUGCCAUUGUCAUGCAAAUGUAGCCAUAGAUGAUAAUAAAUGAAUGGGUGUGACUGUGUUCCAA